CUUGCAUUCACAAGAGAUGGGCUCUGUGGUCUGUGGAAUGAAAUGGUUAAAGAUGGAGAAAUUGUAUACACUGGAACAGAAUCAACCCAGAACGGAUAGCUCCCUCCUGGAAAAGUAGAGACGAGGUUUCACCGUGUUAGCCAGGAUGGUGUCGAUAUCCUGACCUCCUGAUCCACCCGCCAUGGCUUCCCAAAGUGCUGGGAUUACAGGCAUGAGCCACCACGCCCGGCCAAUAUAUUGGUUUCUUUAUGAAAAUUAUACUGGAUCUGUUACAGAUGAUAGUGUCGAACCAAGUGGGACAAAGAAAGAUCUGAAUGACAAAGAGAAAAAAGAUGAAGAAGAAACUCCUGCACCUAUAUAUAGGGCCAAGUCAAUUCUGGACAGCUGGGUAUGGGGCAAGCAACCAGAGUCAUUUUUUACAGGUCAGAACUGUAGAAAUAAUGAGAAAGUGACACUUGUACGCAUAGCUGAUUUGGAGAACCAUAAUAACGAUGGAGGCUUCUGGACUGUGAUUGACGGGAAAGUGUAUGAUAUAAAGGACUUCCAGACACAGUCGUUAACAGAAAAUAGUAUUCUUGCUCAGUUUGCAGGGGAAGACCCAGUGGUAGCUUUGGAAGCUGCUUUGCAGUUUGAAGACACCCGGGAAUCCAUGCACGCAUUUUGUGUUGGCCAGUAUUUGGAGCCUGACCAAGAAAUCGUCACCAUACCAGAUCUGGGGAGUCUCUCUUCACCUCUGAUAGACACAGAGAGGAAUCUGGGCCUGCUUCUCGGAUUACACGCUUCCUAUUUGGCAAUGAGCACACCGCUGUCUCCUGUCGAGAUUGAAUGUGCCAAAUGGCUUCAGUCAUCCAUCUUCUCUGGAGGCCUGCAGACCAGCCAGAUCCACUACAGCUACAACGAGGAGAAAGACGAGGACCACUGCAGCUCCCCAGGGGGCACACCUGCCAGCAAAUCUCGACUCUGCUCCCACAGACGGGCCCUGGGGGACCAUUCCCAGGCAUUUCUGCAAGCCAUUGCAGACAACAACAUUCAGGAUCACAACGUGAAGGACUUUUUGUGUCAAAUAGAAAGGUACUGUAGGCAGUGCCAUUUGACCACACCGAUCAUGUUUCCCCCCGAGCAUCCCGUGGAAGAGGUCGGUCGCUUGCUGUUAUGUUGCCUCUUAAAACAUGAAGAUUUAGGUCAUGUGGCAUUAUCUUUAGUUCAUGCAGGUGCACUUGGUAUUGAGCAAGUAAAGCACAGAACGUUGCCUAAGUCAGUGGUGGAUGUUUGUAGAGUUGUCUACCAAGCAAAAUGUUCGCUCAUUAAGACUCAUCAAGAACAGGACCGUUCUUACAAGGAGGUCUGCGCUCCUGUCAUCGAACGUUUGAGAUUCCUCUUUAAUGAAUUGAGACCUGCUGUUUGUAAUGACCUCUCUAUAAUGUCUAAGUUUAAAUUGUUAAGUUCUUUGCCCCAUUGGAGGAGGAUAGCUCAGAAGAUAAUUCGAGAACCAAGGAAAAAGAGAGUUCCUAAGAAGCCAGAAUCUACGGAUGAUGAAGAAAAAAUUGGAAACGAAGAGAGUGAUUUAGAAGAAGCUUGCAUUUUGCCUCAUAGUCCAAUAAAUGUGGACAAGAGACCCAUUGCAAUUAAAUCACCCAAGGACAAAUGGCAGCCGCUGUUGAGUACUGUUACAGGUGUUCACAAAUACAAGUGGUUGAAGCAGAAUGUGCAGGGUCUUUAUCCGCAGUCUCCACUCCUCAGUACAAUUGCUGAAUUUGCCCUUAAAGAAGAGCCAGUGGAUGUGGAAAAGAGAAAGUGCCUACUAAAACAGUUGGAGAGAGCAGAGGUUCGCCUGGAAGGGAUAGAUACAAUUUUAAAAUUGUAUCUGGUGAGCAAGAAUUUCUUACUUCCAUCUGUGCCAUAUGCAAUGUUUUGUGGAUGGCAAAGACUUAUUCCUGAGGGAAUCGAUAUAGGGGAACCUCUUACUGAUUGUUUAAAGGAUGUUGAUUUGAUCCCGCCUUUUAAUCGGAUGCUGCUGGAAGUCACCUUUGGCAAGCUGUACGCUUGGGCUGUUCAGAACAUUCGAAAUGUUUUGGUGGAUGCCAGUGCCAAAUUUAAAGAGCUUGGUAUCCAGCCGGUUCCCCUGCAAACCAUCACCAAUGAGAACCCAUCGGGACCGAGCCUGGGGACCAUCCCGCAAGCCCACUUCCUCCUGGUGAUGCUCAGCAUGCUCACCCUGCAGCACAGCGCAAACAACCUUGACCUCCUGCUCAAUUCCGGCACGCUGGCCCUCGCUCAGACGGCACUGCGCCUGAUUGGCCCCAGUUGUGACAACGUUGAGGAAGAUAUGAAUGCUUCUGCUCAAGGUGCUUCUGCCACAGUUUUGGAAGAAACAAGGAAGGAAACGGCUCCUGUGCAGCUCCCUGUUUCAGGGCCAGAACUGGCUGCCAUGAUGAAGAUUGGAACAAGGGUCAUGAGAGGAUGGGCCUCCUCCAGGCCUAGGCCGAGUGAUUGGUGAGCUGGGAGAGGACGGGUGGAUAAGAGUCCAGUGGGACACAGGCAGCACCAACUCCUACAGGAUGGGGAAAGAAGGAAAAUACGACCUCAAGCUGGCAGAGCUGCCAGCCCCUGCACAGCCCUCAGCAGAGGAUUCGGACACAGAGGACGACUCUGGUG